CGAGGCUCCUCCUCUGUGGAUGGUCACUGCCCCUCCACCAGGCUUCCUGCUGGAGGAGUUUCCUUCCCAGCCAGGCCGGCCCAGAAGCCAGAUGGUCCCGGGACAGGCCCAGCCCCAGAGCCCAGAGAUGCUGCUGCUGCCCCUGCUGCUGCCCGUGCUGGGGGCGGGGUCCCUGAACAAGGAUCCCAGUUACAGUCUUCAAGUGCAGAGGCAGGUGCCGGUGCCGGAGGGCCUGUGUGUCAUCGUGUCUUGCAACCUCUCCUACCCCCGGGAUGGCUGGGACGAGUCUACUGCUGCUUAUGGCUACUGGUUCAAAGGACGGACCAGCCCAAAGACGGGUGCUCCUGUGGCCACUAACAACCAGAGUCGAGAGGUGGAAAUGAGCACCCGGGACCGAUUCCAGCUCACUGGGGAUCCCGGCAAAGGGAGCUGCUCCUUGGUGAUCAGAGACGCGCAGAGGGAGGAUGAGGCAUGGUACUUCUUUCGGGUGGAGAGAGGAAGCCGUGUGAGACAUAGUUUCCUGAGCAAUGCGUUCUUUCUAAAAGUAACAGCCCUGACUAAGAAGCCUGAUGUCUACAUCCCCGAGACCCUGGAGCCCGGGCAGCCGGUGACGGUCAUCUGUGUGUUUAACUGGGCUUUCAAGAAAUGUCCAGCCCCUUCUUUCUCCUGGACGGGGGCUGCCCUCUCCCCUAGAAGAACCAGACCAAGCACCUCCCACUUCUCAGUGCUCAGCUUCACGCCCAGCCCCCAGGACCACGACACCGACCUCACCUGCCAUGUGGACUUCUCCAGAAAGGGUGUGAGCGCACAGAGGACCGUCCGACUCCGUGUGGCCUAUGCCCCCAAAGACCUUAUUAUCAGCAUUUCACAUGACAACACGUCAGCCCUGGAACUCCAGGGAAACGUCAUAUAUCUGGAAGUUCAGAAAGGCCAGUUCCUGCGGCUCCUCUGUGCUGCUGACAGCCAGCCCCCUGCCACGCUGAGCUGGGUCCUGCAGGACAGAGUCCUCUCCUCGUCCCACCCCUGGGGCCCCAGAACCCUGGGGCUGGAGCUGCGUGGGGUAAGGGCCGGGGAUUCAGGGCGCUACACCUGCCGAGCGGAGAACAGGCUUGGCUCCCAGCAGCAAGCCCUGGACCUCUCUGUGCAGUAUCCUCCAGAGAACCUGAGAGUGAUGGUUUCCCAAGCAAACAGGACAGUCCUGGAAAACCUCGGGAACGGCACAUCCCUCCCGGUCCUGGAGGGCCAAAGCCUGCGCCUGGUCUGUGUCACCCACAGCAGCCCCCCAGCCAGGCUGAGCUGGACCCGGUGGGGACAGACCGUGGGCCCCUCCCAGCCCUCAGACCCCGGGGUCCUGGAGCUGCCACCCAUUCAAAUGGAGCACGAAGGAGAGUUCACCUGCCACGCUCAGCACCCUCUGGGCUCCCAGCACGUCUCUCUCAGCCUCUCCGUGCACUACCCUCCACAGCUGCUGGGCCCCUCCUGCUCCUGGGAGGCUGAGGGUCUGCACUGCAGCUGCUCCUCCCAGGCCAGCCCGGCCCCCUCUCUGCGCUGGUGGCUUGGGGAGGAGCUGCUGGAGGGGAACAGCAGUCAGGGCUCCUUCGAGGUCACCCCCAGCUCAGCCGGGCCCUGGGCCAACAGCUCCCUGAGCCUCCAUGGAGGGCUCAGCUCCGGCCUCAGGCUCCGCUGUAAGGCCUGGAACGUCCACGGGGCCCAGAGUGGCUCUGUCUUCCAGCUGCUACCAGGGAAGCUGGAGCAUGGGGGAGGACUUGGCCUGGGGGCUGCCCUGGGAGCUGGCGUCGCUGCCCUGCUCGCUUUCUGUUCCUGCCUUGUCGUCUUCAGGGUGAAGAUCUGCAGGAAGGAAGCUCGCAAGAGGGCAGCAGCUGAGCAGGACGUGCCCUCCACCCUGGGACCCAUCUCCCAGGGUCACCAGCAUGAAUGCUCGGCAGGCAGCUCCCAAGACCACCCGCCCCCAGGUGCAGCCACCUACACCCCGGGGAAGGGGGAAGAGCAGGAGCUCCACUAUGCCUCCCUCAGCUUCCAGGGCCUGAGGCUCUGGGAGCCUGCGGACCAGGAGGCCCCCAGCACCACCGAGUACUCGGAGAUCAAGAUCCACACAGGACAGCCCCUGAGGGGCCCAGGCUUUGGGCUUCAAUUGGAGAGGGAGAUGUCAGGGAUGGUUCCAAAGUGAAGAGGUCUCCAUGGCAACAGGACACCAGCAAGUGUGUGGGAGUCGCACUGGUGUGACGGCCAGAACUGGACUCAGAUUUCAGCCCCAUCCCCAAUGAAGAGCUUGAGUUUGAAGAUUAUACUUUUUUUGAGACAGGGUCUGACUCUGUCCUCCAGGCCAGAGUCCAGUGGUGCAAUCUCAGCUCACUGUAGCCUCAACCUGCCAGGUUGAAGUGAGCCUCCCAUUUCAGCCUCCCAAGUAGCUGGGACUACAAUUGUGAGCCACCAUGCCAGGCUCAUUGUUAUAUUUUUAGUAGAGACAGGGUUUUGCCAUGUUUCCCUGGCUGGUCUCAGACUCCUGGGCUCAAGCAAUCUGCCCGCCUCUGCCUCCCAAAGUGCUGGGAUUACAGACGUGAGCCACCACAGCUGGCUGAAGAUUAUACUUUCAAUUCAGAGCGAGUUUGAAGAUGACACUUUGAGGCAUCGUGUCUAUGGUUCAUUACUACAGAAGCUUCUCUGGAUGUGUAAAGCACAGGAAACCAGGCAGAGGAGGCACAGGGUGCUCUCCAGAACGAGAAGCCAGCUCCUGGAGUUGUUUGCUGCAACUGCCAUUCCCCGUUGAUGACCAUGCUCUUCCUUCAGAAGAGGGAGAGUGAGAGGACCAAGUCCAAGUGGUUCCCAUUUGAACAUUUAAAAAAAAAAAAAAGGCUGGGCAUGGUGGCUCACGCCUGUAAUCUCAACACUUUGGGAGGCUGAAGUGGGUGGAUCACAAGUCAGGAGUUCAAGACCAGCCUGGGCAAGAUGGUGAAACCCCAUCUCUACUAAAAAUACAAAAAUUAGCCGGGCAUGGUGGCGGGCGCCUAAAAUCCCAGCUACUCGGGAGACUAGGCAGAGAAUUGGUUGAACCCGGGAGGUGGAGGUUGCAGUGAGCCGAGAUCGUCCCACUGCACUCCAGCCUGGGCAACAGAGUGAGACUCUGUUUCUAAAUAAAUAAAUGAAUAAAUAAA